AUGCGUGGAUUGUCGUCUUCUGUCCAAGUUGGUCGCUUCCCUGCGCCAAAGGUAAGCGGGCCGUUAUCCAUUUGUGUUGUUCGCCAGCUAGGCCUGGCCUCGUCCCGCUUCGCUCGUGAGCAGUAGCCAACAUGUCAGGGUGGGAGUCAUAUUACAAAACCGAGGGCGAUGAAGAAGCAGAGGAAGAACAAGAAGAGAACCUUGAAGCAAGUGGAGACUAUAAAUAUUCAGGAAGAGAUAGUUUGAUUUUUUUGGUUGAUGCCUCCAAGGCUAUGUUUGAAUCUCAGAGUGAAGAUGAGUUGACACCUUUUGACAUGAGCAUCCAGUGUAUCCAAAGUGUGUACAUCAGUAAGAUCAUAAGCAGUGAUCGAGAUCUCUUGGCUGUGGUGUUCUAUGGUACCGAGAAAGACAAAAAUUCAGUGAAUUUUAAAAAUAUUUACGUCUUACAGGAGCUGGAUAAUCCAGGUGCAAAACGAAUUCUAGAGCUUGACCAGUUUAAGGGGCAGCAGGGACAAAAACGUUUCCAAGACAUGAUGGGCCACGGAUCUGACUACUCACUCAGUGAAGUGCUGUGGGUCUGUGCCAACCUCUUUAGUGAUGUCCAAUUCAAGAUGAGUCAUAAGAGGAUCAUGCUGUUCACCAAUGAAGACAACCCCCAUGGCAAUGACAGUGCCAAAGCCAGCCGGGCCAGGACCAAAGCCGGUGAUCUCCGAGAUACAGGCAUCUUCCUUGACUUGAUGCACCUGAAGAAACCUGGGGGCUUUGACAUAUCCUUGUUCUACAGAGAUAUCAUCAGCAUAGCAGAGGAUGAGGACCUCAGGGUUCACUUUGAGGAAUCCAGCAAGCUAGAAGACCUGUUGCGGAAGGUUCGCGCCAAGGAGACCAGGAAGCGAGCACUCAGCAGGUUAAAGCUGAAGCUCAACAAAGAUAUAGUGAUCUCUGUGGGCAUUUAUAAUCUGGUCCAGAAGGCUCUCAAGCCUCCUCCAAUAAAGCUCUAUCGGGAAACAAAUGAACCAGUGAAAACCAAGACCCGGACCUUUAAUACAAGUACAGGCGGUUUGCUUCUGCCUAGCGAUACCAAGAGGUCUCAGAUCUAUGGGAGUCGUCAGAUUAUACUGGAGAAAGAGGAAACAGAAGAGCUAAAACGGUUUGAUGAUCCAGGUUUGAUGCUCAUGGGUUUCAAGCCGUUGGUACUGCUGAAGAAACACCAUUACCUGAGGCCCUCCCUGUUCGUGUACCCAGAGGAGUCGCUGGUGAUUGGGAGCUCAACCCUGUUCAGUGCUCUGCUCAUCAAGUGUCUGGAGAAGGAGGUUGCAGCAUUGUGCAGAUACACACCCCGCAGGAACAUCCCUCCUUAUUUUGUGGCUUUGGUGCCACAGGAAGAAGAGUUGGAUGACCAGAAAAUUCAGGUGACUCCUCCAGGCUUCCAGCUGGUCUUUUUACCCUUUGCUGAUGAUAAAAGGAAGAUGCCCUUUACUGAAAAAAUCAUGGCAACUCCAGAGCAGGUGGGCAAGAUGAAGGCUAUCGUUGAGAAGCUUCGCUUCACAUACAGAAGUGACAGCUUUGAGAACCCCGUGCUGCAGCAGCACUUCAGGAACCUGGAGGCCUUGGCCUUGGAUUUGAUGGAGCCGGAACAAGCAGUGGACCUGACAUUGCCCAAGGUUGAAGCAAUGAAUAAAAGACUGGGCUCCUUGGUGGAUGAGUUUAAGGAGCUUGUUUACCCACCAGAUUACAAUCCUGAAGGGAAAGUUACCAAGAGAAAACACGAUAAUGAAGGUUCUGGAAGCAAAAGGCCCAAGGUGGAGUAUUCAGAAGAGGAGCUGAAGACCCACAUCAGCAAGGGUACGCUGGGCAAGUUCACUGUGCCCAUGCUGAAAGAGGCCUGCCGGGCUUACGGGCUGAAGAGUGGGCUGAAGAAGCAGGAGCUGCUGGAAGCCCUCACCAAGCACUUCCAGGACUGACCAGAGGCCGCGCGUCCAGCUGCCCUUCCGCAGUGUGGCCAGGCUGCCUGGCCUUGUCCUCAGCCAGUUAAAAUGUGUUUCUCCUGAGCUAGGAAGAGUCUACCCGACAUAAGUCGAGGGACUUUAUGUUUUUGAGGCUUUCUGUUGCCAUGGUGAUGGUGUAGCCCUCCCACUUUGCUGUUCCUUACUUUACUGCCUGAAUAAAGAGCCCUAAGUUUGUACUAUA